AAACAAAACAGAAAUGCAACGCUUUAGAGUACCCACGGAAAACUUGUUUACCUUGUCACCAUGAGUAAAAGUUAAUUCCCACUCCUGAAGAGAGCAAACCAACUCUGAAAGAGAGUGAAAAUGCAGACAAGACAGUUAUCAGAUAAUGGCUAUCUGGACGAGAGAUUCUUUCGUUUGACAGCAGUUUGGUUGUUGGGAGUUCCAGUUCAGCUCCUGCACAGUUGCUCUGUACAAAUCCUCCUCCAUAUUUGCUUAGAGAAAACGUGUUGCCAUCCCAUCAUGAAGGAAGCUGCCUGAGAGUUUUUAACCAUUACAGCCGUGAUGAUGAAAGAGUGAAGAACCGCCUCUAAGUUAAAAAGUGCACCCAGAGAUAAGGUUCGUUCUCAAUGCCCUGCCGCUGCUUCUCAUCGCAUGGCCACCGCAUUUCUCAGGCCAGGCACAUUGAGCAUUGGUCCUGUGCCUGACGCUAUGCUAGAUGCUGGGGUUGCAGCCACGAGCAUAGACACGACAGACACGGUCCUCGCCAUCUUCUGUUGAGUACUGGUCGGAACAAGAGGAUCGUCUGUAGACAGGCUACAGAUUGUUUUAGAUUGAAGUUUCCUGUCAUGUUCACUCAUCUUUAAAUCCUCAUAGUGAAAAAGGAUAUGAUCAUCGUGGCGCAUGUAUUACUCAUCCUUUUGGGGGCCACUGAGAUACUGCAAGCUGACUUACUUCCUGAUGAAAAGAUUUCACUUCUCCCACCUGUCAAUUUCACCAUUAAAGUUACUGGUUUGGCUCAAGUUCUUUUACAAUGGAAACCAAAUCCUGAUCAAGAGCAAAGGAAUGUUAAUCUAGAAUAUCAAGUGAAAAUAAACGCUCCAAAAGAAGAUGACUAUGAAACCAGAAUCACUGAAAGCAAAUGUGUAACCAUCCUCCACAAAGGCUUUUCAGCAAGUGUGCGGACCAUCCUGCAGAACGACCACUCACUACUGGCCAGCAGCUGGGCUUCUGCUGAACUUCAUGCCCCACCAGGGUCUCCUGGAACCUCAAUUGUGAAUUUAACUUGCACCACAAACACUACAGAAGACAAUUAUUCACGUUUAAGGUCAUACCAAGUUUCCCUUCACUGCACCUGGCUUGUUGGCACAGAUGCCCCUGAGGACACGCAGUAUUUUCUCUACUAUAGGUAUGGCUCUUGGACUGAAGAAUGCCAAGAAUACAGCAAAGACACACUGGGGAGAAAUAUCGCAUGCUGGUUUCCCAGGACUUUUAUCCUCAGCAAAGGGCGUGACUGGCUUGCGGUGCUUGUUAACGGCUCCAGCAAGCACUCUGCUAUCAGGCCCUUUGAUCAGCUGUUUGCCCUUCACGCCAUUGAUCAAAUAAAUCCUCCACUGAAUGUCACAGCAGAGAUUGAAGGAACUCGUCUCUCUAUCCAAUGGGAGAAACCAGUGUCUGCUUUUCCAAUCCAUUGCUUUGAUUAUGAAGUAAAAAUACACAAUACAAGGAAUGGAUAUUUGCAGAUAGAAAAAUUGAUGACCAAUGCAUUCAUCUCAAUAAUUGAUGAUCUUUCUAAGUACGAUGUUCAAGUGAGAGCAGCAGUGAGCUCCAUGUGCAGAGAGGCAGGGCUCUGGAGUGAGUGGAGCCAACCUAUUUAUGUGGGAAAUGAUGAACACAAGCCCUUGAGAGAGUGGUUUGUCAUUGUGAUUAUGGCAACCAUCUGCUUCAUCUUGUUAAUUCUCUCGCUUAUCUGUAAAAUAUGUCAUUUAUGGAUCAAGUUGUUUCCACCAAUUCCAGCACCAAAAAGUAAUAUCAAAGAUCUCUUUGUAACCACUAACUAUGAGAAAGCUGGGUCCAGUGAGACGGAAAUUGAAGUCAUCUGUUAUAUAGAGAAGCCUGGAGUUGAGACCCUGGAGGAUUCUGUGUUUUGACUGUCACUUUGGCAUCCUCUGAUGAACUCACACAUGCCUCAGUGCCUCAGUGAAAAGAACAGGGAUGCUGGCUCUUGGCUAAGAGGUGUUCAGAAUUUAGGCAACACUCAAUUUACCUGCGAAGCAAUACACCCAGACACACCAGUCUUGUAUCUCUUAAAAGUAUGGAUGCUUCAUCCAAAUCGCCUCACCUACAGCAGGGAAGUUGACUCAUCCAAGCAUUUUGCCAUGUUUUUUCUCCCCAUGCCGUACAGGGUAGCACCUCCUCACCUGCCAAUCUUUGCAAUUUGCUUGACUCACCUCAGACUUUUCAUUCACAACAGACAGCUUUUAAGGCUAACGUCCAGCUGUAUUUACUUCUGGCUGUGCCCGUUUGGCUGUUUAAGCUGCCAAUUGUAGCACUCAGCUACCAUCUGAGGAAGAAAGCAUUUUGCAUCAGCCUGGAGUGAACCAUGAACUUGGAUUCAAGACUGUCUUUUCUAUAGCAAGUGAGAGCCACAAAUUCCUCACCCCCCUACAUUCUAGAAUGAUCUUUUUCUAGGUAGAUUGUGUAUGUGUGUGUAUGAGAGAGAGAGAGAGAGAGAGAGAGAGAGAAAUUAUCUCAAGCUCCAGAGGCCUGAUCCAGGAUACAUCAUUUGAAACCAACUAAUUUAAAAGCAUAAUAGAGCUAAUAUAUCACCCCAUAUCAAAAGAGACGACAGAUUUUGUUCAAAUAUUAUAUUCUUGAAGGAAGCCUUAAUAUUCUGGAAAUGUGCUGAGGAAGUCAUUGAGCAUAAUUCAAUCAUGAAAGGGACCACUGAAUCAAGAAUGAACUUUCUGAAGAGAUGUUUGCUGCCAAAGACUUCAGAACAACUUGUUGGUCAAGUAAUGCCAGAUCAAUCCUAGUCUCUCAAGUUUGGAAAAGUUUCUACAAGGCCAUUCCAUCAAAUAUCCCAAUAUACACAGAAAUUCUUCUUCCUAACAUCUUCAUAUAUGAGUCUGCAUCCAGAUUGGAGGCCUUUGUGGUGGGUGGUGGACUGCAGGUGGAACCAAGCACAGGUGUGCCCUGGGCAGAGGUGGGCAAGAGGAAGGAACCCAAACAGUGCUGAUUCCACAUGGCCCUUGGUCAAGAAGCUGAAGGCCUAGAAAGGAGGUAACAGUGCCCAGAAUCCCCACCUGGCACACUCUUUAAAUGCUUUCUGGAGGUGUUUUAGUCAGUUUUGAUCCAUCGGUGGGGACACACUGACUACCAUAUAUUUCCAGGUUUGUUUGUUUUCUUAACUAACCUGUAAUUAUCCACUGUAACUAGCAGAGGGUUGAACCCUGGGUAAUAGGCACAGAAACAUCUUGAAUCUUGACAAGCCUGCACUGUCUUAUAGUAAUCUGUAUUACUGUCCCAUUUUAUAGUUGCAGUUACUAAGGUUCAGAGAAGUUGAUAGGAAAUGGCAUAGUGAGGAGUUGAAUACCAGGCUCAGGUAAAAGUGACCCCAGAAAUGUGCAGAGGAGUGUCAGGGAAAGCUGAGGCCUGCUUAGGGGUGUGGCUGAGAAGGCAACACCCAUGGAGGUGCUGCAAUAGUUGGCAAAAUGUUUAAAAUGUUUGGUCACUCAAAUGAUUCAUAAUCUCAAACCUGUUUUUGUUUUUUUUUUUUUUUUUUUUUGUGGGGUGGGUGGUGGAGACAGUCUUGUUCUGUCUCCCAGGCUAGAGUGUAGUGAUGUGAUCUUAGCUCACUACAACCUCCCUGUCCUGGGCUCAAGCCAUCCUCCUCCCUCACCCUCCCAAGUAGCUGGGACUACAGGUGCAUAACACCAUUCCCAGCUCUUUUUUGUAUUUUUUUUUGUAAAGCUGGGGUUUUGCCAUGCUGUCUAGGUUCAUCUCGAACUCCUGGGCUCAAGCGAUACACCGGCCUCAGCCUUCCAAAGUACUGGGAUUACAGGCAUGAACCACCAUUCCUGGCCAGGAAACUGUAUUUGUAAUGAACACCUUAGGUCAGAAUCAGAGGCGCCUGGAGGGCUCCUUAAGACACAGAGGAGUGGGCUCCAUUCUUAGAGUCUCUAACUGAAUAGGUCUGGGUGAGGUCUGAAAAGCUGCGUUUCUAACAAGUUCUCAGGUGAUGCUCAUGCUGCUGGUCUCCAGGACACACUCGGAGAACUGCUGCUCCAGGAGAGUCUUAUGAAUACCAAAAUUUGAAAAUCAGCCGCUGAAGGAAGAUGUGACAGAAAAGUCCUGUCCCCAGAAAACUGUCCUUUUGGGGCGGCUUGGAGCACCCUGUCUGAUCUCUUUCAAACCACAACCCAGACAGUUGGCAUUGUGGAAACUGCCUCUGCUUAGGAGGCAGGAACAGAAGCAGGGAGCUCCCCCUCCACAAAUGUGGCCAGCUCUUCAGUGCUUGGUGUGGUGCCCACUUCAGACUCCUCCCUCCACUCAGCAGCCAUAGAUCACCUGGGCUCUGUGGAGCUCCUUGCCACACUUCCCUGAGCUGGUACCGUUAUCUGGCCCUUGGUAUAUGUGUUUCAGGAGCAACACAAAGUAGCCCAUUGGCCUCCUUGGUGGAUUGGGAACUCCUUCCUCCCUUCUUGCCCUGUGCAACUCAUAGUCAUUCUUUGGGAACCCGUAACCAUCAUCACUUCCUCCAUGAAGCCUUCAAAAGCAGAGUUGGUUGAUCCCGCCUCUGGAUUCUCAUUCUGGGCCUCAUACCCGUGUUAGAGCUACUGCAUUGUAGAAUAUACCAUUAACAGCUGGGAGGCCUCCCCUCUAGACUGCGGCUUCCAGGAGGAUGGAGCUUGUGUGAAAUACGUCUUUUUAUCUGCAGUGUCUAGGACAGUAUCUGACUUAAGAAAAUAUAAAUGUUUCUUAAACCCUCUGUCAGCCCUGAUACGGCACCUUGUAUAUAGGUUAGACUGAACAGUAUUUGGCAGAGAUCCUCAAGGCCUACAAUAAUGACAGGGGGAGGAAGCUGGGUAUCUAAUGAGAAUGCGGUUAGUUAGAAGCAACCAGGAGACACAUGUGCCUAACAACUGGGCUACUGCAACCUGGAUGUUUUUGCUGCCAAAGUGUCUAAAUGGUUAUGUAUAAAUUGCUGUGUAAGAGGCAUUUCAGAAGUGGCUCACUGUGAGUGGUCUAUACUGUUCUCACCAGCCUUGUCAUAGCAAGUCAAAGAGUUUGAAAUUCACUUAACAGUAAACACCAUCAGCAGCAGGUUGAUGUAAGGUAAAGUCAUGAUAUUGGCUCCCAUCUCUUGCCAUCUCUCACUAGGACGAGUGUAGAGAGUCACUUUUCUCCUAGAGCCUCCACAGCCACGGGAUCAGAACAAACAUGCUUUUCCAAGAUAUCCGUUCCAAUAGGGAUUUUUAGCCCAAUUUCUUUCCUUGGCAUUUGGAAUUCACUGCGUGCAGCAUGGGGGAGUGCUGGGGAGACUGGAGGGUGAAGGUCACAUUUGCCAACAGCCCGACCACCUGAGCCUCAUUGAAAUGCCUCAGACCUCAAGCUAUUCAUGCAGGCUGGGGAAGAAUCCACGUGGGCAAAGAACAUCCUGAUUAAAAAUCCAAACGUUUUCAUGGUGAGACUUCUAUGUGUCAGGACCAUCUGCUGGUGGAAUUAAGAAGCCUGAGGUGCUAAUUUGUUAAAGAAAAAGUAGAUAUCUGGAAGUGAGAACAGAGAACUGAAAACAAUCUCUGAUGGCACAAGUAAAGGUGAAAAACCUAAUUAGAAUAGGACUUGGUGCUAGCCUAAGGACUGUAGCUAUUCCUGCUUCUACAUCCUUCAAAUUGAGUACCAGGGUGCAAAUUUUUUCAAAACCAUUCCUUCCUUUGGAAUUUUGUAUUGUACUAUAAGACAAUCAUGCUUAUCUCCUGUUUUGUAGGUAAUAGAUGUGAAUAUAAAUAUGUUUCAGAAUGAGAAAUAUUAAACAUAAAUGACAGUGAA